GCGUGCCGUCAGCUCGCCGGGCACCGCGGCCUCGCCCUCGCCCUCCGCCCCUGCGCCUGCACCGCGUAGACCGACCCCCCCCCAGCGCGCCCACCCGGUAGAGGACCCCCGCCCGUGCCCCGACCGGUCCCCGCCUUUUUGUAAAACUUAAAGCGGGCGCAGCAUUAACGCUUCCCGCCCCGGUGACCUCUCAGGGGUCUCCCCGCCAAAGGUGCUCCGCCGCUAAGGAACAUGGCGAAGGUGGAGCAGGUCCUGAGCCUCGAGCCGCAGCACGAGCUCAAAUUCCGAGGUCCCUUCACCGAUGUUGUCACCACCAACCUAAAGCUUGGCAACCCGACAGACCGAAAUGUGUGUUUUAAGGUGAAGACUACAGCACCACGUAGGUACUGUGUGAGGCCCAACAGCGGAAUCAUCGAUGCAGGGGCCUCAAUUAAUGUAUCUGUGAUGUUACAGCCUUUCGAUUAUGAUCCCAAUGAGAAAAGUAAACACAAGUUUAUGGUUCAGUCUAUGUUUGCUCCAACUGACACUUCAGAUAUGGAAGCAGUAUGGAAGGAGGCAAAACCGGAAGACCUUAUGGAUUCAAAACUUAGAUGUGUGUUUGAAUUGCCAGCAGAGAAUGAUAAACCACAUGAUGUAGAAAUAAAUAAAAUUAUAUCCACAACUGCAUCAAAGACAGAAACACCAAUAGUGUCUAAGUCUCUGAGUUCUUCUUUGGAUGACACCGAAGUUAAGAAGGUUAUGGAAGAAUGUAAGAGGCUGCAAGGUGAAGUUCAGAGGCUACGGGAGGAGAACAAGCAGUUCAAGGAAGAAGAUGGACUGCGGAUGAGGAAGACAGUGCAGAGCAACAGCCCCAUUUCAGCAUUAGCCCCAACUGGGAAGGAAGAAGGCCUUAGCACCCGGCUCUUGGCUCUGGUGGUUUUGUUCUUUAUCGUUGGUGUAAUUAUUGGGAAGAUUGCCUUGUAGAGGUAGCAUGCACAGGAUGGUAAAUUGGAUUGGUGGAUCCACCAUAUCAUGGGAUUUAAAUUUAUCAUAACCAUGUGUAAAAAGAAAUUAAUGUAUGAUGACAUCUCACAGGUCUUGCCUUUAAAUUACCCCUCCCUGCACACACAUACACAGAUACACACACACAAAUAUAAUGUAACGAUCUUUUAGAAAGUUAAAAAUGUAUAGUAACUGAUUGAGGGGGAAAAGAAUGAUCUUUAUUAAUGACAAGGGAAACCAUGAGUAAUGCCACAAUGGCAUAUUGUAAAUGUCAUUUUAAACAUUGGUAGGCCUUGGUACAUGAUGCUGGAUUACCUCUCUUAAAAUGACACCCUUCCUCGCCUGUUGGUGCUGGCCCUUGGGGAGCUGGAGCCCAGCAUGCUGGGGAGUGCGGUCAGCUCCACACAGUAGUCCCCACGUGGCCCACUCCCGGCCCAGGCUGCUUUCCGUGUCUUCAGUUCUGUCCAAGCCAUCAGCUCCUUGGGACUGAUGAACAGAGUCAGAAGCCCAAAGGAAUUGCACUGUGGCAGCAUCAGACGUACUCGUCAUAAGUGAGAGGCGUGUGUUGACUGAUUGACCCAGCGCUUUGGAAAUAAAUGGCAGUGCUUUGUUCACUUAAAGGGACCAAGCUAAAUUUGUAUUGGUUCAUGUAGUGAAGUCAAACUGUUAUUCAGAGAUGUUUAAUGCAUAUUUAACUUAUUUAAUGUAUUUCAUCUCAUGUUUUCUUAUUGUCACAAGAGUACAGUUAAUGCUGCGUGCUGCUGAACUCUGUUGGGUGAACUGGUAUUGCUGCUGGAGGGCUGUGGGCUCCUCUGUCUCUGGAGAGUCUGGUCAUGUGGAGGUGGGGUUUAUUGGGAUGCUGGAGAAGAGCUGCCAGGAAGUGUUUUUUCUGGGUCAGUAAAUAACAACUGUCAUAGGGAGGGAAAUUCUCAGUAGUGACAGUCAACUCUAGGUUACCUUUUUUAAUGAAGAGUAGUCAGUCUUCUAGAUUGUUCUUAUACCACCUCUCAACCAUUACUCACACUUCCAGCGCCCAGGUCCAAGUCUGAGCCUGACCUCCCCUUGGGGACCUAGCCUGGAGUCAGGACAAAUGGAUCGGGCUGCAGAGGGUUAGAAGCGAGGGCACCAGCAGUUGUGGGUGGGGAGCAAGGGAAGAGAGAAACUCUUCAGCGAAUCCUUCUAGUACUAGUUGAGAGUUUGACUGUGAAUUAAUUUUAUGCCAUAAAAGACCAACCCAGUUCUGUUUGACUAUGUAGCAUCUUGAAAAGAAAAAUUAUAAUAAAGCCCCAAAAUUAAGAAUUCUUUUGUCAUUUUGUCACAUUUGCUCUAUGGGGGGAAUUAUUAUUUUAUCAUUUUUAUUAUUUUGCCAUUGGAAGGUUAACUUUAAAAUGAGCCCUAUCACUGAGAAAUACGUGUUUCAUGAUUUAACUCUGUGUGUGUGUGUGUGUGUGUGUGUGUGUGUGUGUGUAUUUUUUUUUUGGUUGUCUUCAGCUGACAGUAUGAAAAAUGAAACUGCUGAAAAAGCUGAGCACCUGGUCACCCUUGGCCUUCCAUUGCUUUGGCCUUCAGUAAAAAGCAGCCUCCCUUCUAGGUCAGGGAACCAUGCCAUUGAGACUAGUAACGGGCGUUCUGGGCACAGUCCCACUGUGCACAGGUUUGAGAGGACAAGUUCAUCAGAAGGAAGGCAGUCCUUAGAAGUCACAUACGUUGAGCCACGUUGCUCCUAAGCCUGGCUCUGUCAAGCUGGGUCAGGGGCCUUGAAACUGGAGAAGUGGAAGUCUAUGGUUGGUCUGAGUAAGUAACUUCCUGUCUUCAUGAAAAAAGUUGACUUUGAAUCCCAGGUACUCACAGAAAUGGUGAACAGACUUAGUUGUUACCCAGGCACCCAUGGAUUGUGUUGAGUGUGCAGACAGGGAGGCCACCCCAAUAGGAAUUCGUCUCCAGGAUUUUUCCCAUGUGUCCCCCAGUACUUAUAAAAGGGAGUGAAAAGACCGAGCUGUAAGGCAUGUGCCUUCUGCCACCUGACUUUCCGUGAGGGGACUAAAAUUUACUAAUUGUAGUUGCUGCAGCCAGUUAAGUCCUGUAGCUUCCAGGCCCUCAUGUCUUUGAUAGGAGAGUGCUUAGGUGGUCCCCAACAGUGCCUAGGGGUACAGUACAGUCCCAUUACACUAGAGCAGGGCUCUAUUUAUUUUUAAAGGAUAUGGCCGUGUGUUUUGAUAAAACUUUAUUCACAAAAACAGCCGGGUCAUGGGAUUUGGCUUGUGAGUCUGUAACAGUUCUUAAAAAGAAUAUCUGAGAAACUACUCUGUUUUAGACCUUUGAAGGUGAUUUAGAGUUUUGUGUACAUCUAGGAGAAGGUGUUCAGCUUCUCAGAGGAUGUGGACAUUUUGGUUGCAGCUAAAAAUCAGUCUCUGAAGUCUCUCUCCCUUCUAGAGGUUAGGACUUGGUGAACAUGUUUGUGGGCCUUUUGACUGAGUGGCAGAAGGAAACUGCUCAGGAAGAGAAACAGGUGACUGAUGGGAAGGUUGAUUAUUUUCUCAGUCAUCCUGGCAGCCAAAAAUGUGCCAGGAAAAGAAAGAAUGUGGAGCACGCGUGGCUCCUGGAGGACUUGGAGAUGCAUGCACAUUUAGGGUGUUUUCCCUAGAAUUACAUAAUGAAAAAAAGAAUAAGGCAAAGAGGAGGUGAAUAUGGGGCCUGUCACAACGGCCUGCCCUGCCCCAAGAGGGUUAAGAGUCAGAUAAUCGGGACGAAACUGGCAUGGAAAGAGCGAGCCUAGGGAGGAUGCCGCUGGGCAGUGUGCAUGGGGGAGCUGCUGCCAGGCUGCCCUCCAGUCUGCUCCUGUGGUUACUGGCUCCACAGCACCUCAGAGAGGGCGGCCCUGGCUUCAGAAAUGCCAGCCAUAGUGCUCACAAAUGCAGAAGAGAUGGAAGCGGUGACAGAAUCCUGAAAGUUUUUAUUGAUUGAAGUUUUAAAUUGGUAACUUAAGCUUCCUUGGCACGAUACAAAAUACCUCUUAAAGACAGCAGGCUUUUUUAUUUGUAGGUGUGAGGAACUGGCUUUAACUUUUUUCUCCUCCUAGUUUGCAUGUUUUCCUUCUCUCGUCUUCUGAACUGCUGGCACCAGCAGUAAUACAUACUGAUAAAAUCAAAAUUGAUUUUUACCAGUGGCCAGUUUAUGGCUAGAGAGACGACUUAUACCUCCAUAACACAGAAGGGGGAAAAAUGAAGAACCUCCAGUGAUCCGUGAAAACCUAAACGCUUUCAAACAAAUCCCAGGAACAGAAUUGCUAUCGAAAGAUAUCAUUGCCCAGUUUGCAGGCUAUGUUGAGUCAGAUAGAACUGAAUGUAGUGAGAGCUCAGAGCUACAGAGCCUUUCAGAUGAAUUUGAAAACAGACUCUGUGUGUGUGUGCAUGUGUGCAUGUGUGCAUGUGUGGCAUAUGUGCCGUAUGUCAGUAGCUUGACAGUUUUCAAAUCGUGCCUAUAUUUUUUUGCAUACACAAAUUUUUGUGUUUGCAAACUCAGAAUCCAUGCCAAAAUACAAUGUUAUAUGUCAUUUUCAGCUCCUUCUCUAAAGGAAUGGCCCAUUUCUCAUUGUAGUUUGAGAAAUACAUGUAUGAAGAGAUAGGGGUCUUGGGCUUCCCAGUGUCACUUUGAACACCUGAAUAACAUUUAACUCCUGAGACCUUCUCGGUGUAGAGGCCACUGCUUCCCCCUGCUGGAGAUGGCAUUUCAUUGAAGGGCCUCUCGUGGCUUUCCCUGCCCCCGGCUGUCUGGCCUGAAGAAGGAGAAAGAACCAAACUGAACUAUGAAAAGUUACCACUCUGAGGAGACCUCUCUUAAUUAACACUUGGGGCCAUGUUUGCUGUUGUUGAGAAGGAGUGUUCUCAAAGAUGAGCUGGAAUGGAAUUGUAUUUAGAAAGGCCCCUGCAAAGUAUAUAGAUGGAUGACUCUAGUUCAUGACAUACAAAUCCCAUAAGGCCAACGACCACUCUUCUGGAACACCAAGAGCAGCUCUGAGAUCAUGCUGGCCCUACGCGAAUUGAGUUUCUGUGGCCUAAUUGGAUUUGGAGAACGCCUUCCCUGGCCCCUUUUCCUCAGACAGAUCUGCUCUGAUAGGAACCUUUUCAAGAAAGUUACUGUUGUUUCAAUGCCACUCCUUACCUGUAUAGAACAUUUCCAAUACAUUCGCUCAUUGAACUUAAUCCUUGCAACUGUGACUGGGGGGUAGAUGGCUCUGUUUGCAUACGAAGAAAUAAAGGCUCCAGGAGGUUAAAUCGGGCAACUUUUUAGAACUAAAUCAGUCUCUGUAAGGCCUACAUUGCUAAGAUACCAUUUCAGCUCUGAAAAUCUGCUUCAGGGAAGUGAGUGGAUGAGGCCUUCCUGCCUCAGCUACUCUGCCCGUCUGUACAUCUUUUGUGUCUGCCUCCGUACCUUAUUCAGUUAUUUUCACACUAAAGUAAGUAGAAUUAAGACUGUAGUUCAGAUGCUUUUUCUUUUUCUGUUGGAAACUGAACACACUACAGACAGUGAAAAAAGGUACAUAUUCCAUUUUCUCAUUGCCUGAAGAUCUCUGCUGAUGCUCCUGGAGAAUGACUUUGGGGGCUUUAGAAAGAAUAUUGCCAGUCCGUCUCGGCAAGGAGAUGAUGGGAGCGCUUUAUAUGGAGGCUUUACAUGACUUGUAAAUUAAAUGUGAAUGAGGGCAGUUGAUUAAAAUUGGUAUUACAGAAGGGCCCUGCUGAGGUUUGAAAACAGCUGAGCUGCUGAUGUCUCAGGCCUUUCCCUGAAUUAGCACUGCGGUUCUCCAGGAUAUCAGCAAAGAGGGCAAGUAAUAGAAGCCCCUGAUAAGGAGCGUCAGCCGACAGGCAAGCUUGGGAGGCUGUGGGAAUGGGUCUGCCCCCAGCUUCACAGACCUCUUCCUCCAGCCUCUGAAUCCCAUUAGCCACAGCCUAGAACAUUAGCUGAGCUGCACAAGCUCACCCACCCCUGUGCCAGGGGGCCCUGACCUCCCUCCAUGCCAUGUUUUUGGCUGUAUCUACGGCACUUAACAAUAGGGGCUUUUUAUUUUCAUUACAGAGAUAUUUUGAAAAAUUUAAAAGACAUGAACUCACAUAAACAGUUAUGGAUGAUAGUUAAAAGAGAAACGGGUGGAGGUGGAUGAGAGGUUGUCUUCAUGAAUAUAAUUACUUGAGAUUUUUUUUUCUUAAUGGAAUUAGUUUAUUAGAAAAUGUCUGUGUUAAAUCCGUAGAAAAGGAAGAAAAGUGUAGCAACAAAAAUGUAGCCAUUAUCUAACUUGCCAUAAAUAUUUGCAGUUAUGAUACCUUGGAAUGUUGCCACGAUAUGGAUUGCUUUGAUUAAAAGAUGUCAGUUGAAUAAAACAGUACUGUGGGAGAAUCGCUUUCUGCUGCUAGAUAAAUGCUGAUGUUUAUUUUUAAACCAGGAAACAUUGAUCCUGUAACAAUGCCCGAUUACAAUUGCUUUAUUACACCCCAGGGCUGAUGGAGAUGUAAUCACUUGGCUAAUGGAUGUGGGUGCAGGACAGAUGCUCGCUUGCUGGCCUGCUUUCCUGCUUGCAUUCUGAUGAGCUGCAGGAGUGCGCCUGGCCUUCUGCAGGUGGAGCUGCUGUCAGAGCUUCGUUUCACUGAUACCCAAAGCCAUGUCUGACUGAAAUAAAACAGGUUCCCUUUUUUUUUCCCUUUGGAAAAUGCCAACUAAGGGAGACUAAUCAGAUAUCUUAACACAAUUUCAUCCAGGCUUAGUGCUAACAAGAUUGCGGGGCUUUUUAGGGUUUAAGAAGAUGAGAAAUGAGUGUGCACGUUUCACACGUUGACUUGCCGGUUUUUCCAUGUCAUACAAAAAAGUCCUGGCUGUUUCUCCGAACUGGCUGCCUGCAUUCCCGUCUUUCUUUUGUUUUUAAGAAAUAGACUGAAUUCAGCUGUUAAUCCUCUAGUACAGUAUCCAUGUUAAAAUGUUUUUCCAUUGCAUCUUUUAUGUGAAUUCAAAGGUCAGAAUUUAUUGUCUGUGAUAUUGAGACCAUGUGUACAAGAACUACUUUUUGCUUUUCAUCAUUCACUCCUUAGCAAACGUUUCGUAAGUACCCUCUGUCUGUUUGCUACUAUAUGAGGUGCUGCGAAAUUAGUGGGCGUGGCUUUUUAUAUUUUUCAUUCGUGUGUAGCCUAAGUAAGGUGACUCAAGAUGAUACACCGAGAGAAAAAUGCAAAAUAUAUUUGGUUCUCAUUUCUGUUGCUGUCGUUUCCUUUUUAAAGACGAUUUAUCAACUGCUGCCAUUUGGAACUUCCUAUAAGAAACUAAAAAUGAUCUAUUUCAGUGUUCCUUUCGCCUUUCCUCUGCUUUCUGAAUAAAUGGUUUCAGUAACCCAUGCUGUUCUCUCCCUAUUCUACGUCUUUCUCCCUAUGUUGAAAAAAGAUUCCCACAGUUUCUGAUGUGUGUGUUUAUAGUCUUCAAUGUAUGUUAACAUGUUAGGAACUGAGUAUCUUAAGAGAUGUCUUAGAAUGCUUUAGUUUUCAUAAUUUGUCCUUUAUGUAUUUUUCAUUGUAUUUGCUGUUUUGACAUGGAAGUAAUUUAAAAAGUUGGUGCAGGAAAGGACUCUUUACUGUUGCACAUUUUGGUUUUCUGAUAUGUAAUAAAUUCAUGGCUUGGCAGCUGACAUGAUGUUUCCCAGAGAGAAGGAGAUGUAUUUCUGCAGGGUCCAGACCAAAAGAGCCAUUUACAGCAUGUUCUCCCAUGUUCCAUUAUCAGCCUGAUGAAACCUGCCCUGCCAAGGCAUAAACUUUUGUACUAGCUGUCUCCAUAUUAUGUUCAAUAAAUUCUGUGCUCUGAAUAUAUUUAAA